GAGGAAGAAGCGGAGGAGGCGGCUCCCGCGCUCGCAGGGCCGUGCCACCUGCCCGCCCGCCCGCUCGCUCGCUCGCCCGCCGCGCCGCGCUGCCGACCGCCAGCAUGCUGCCGAGAGUGGGCUGCCCCGCGCUGCCGCUGCCGCCGCCGCCGCUGCUGCCGCUGCUGCUGCUGCUACUGGGCGCGAGUGGCGGCGGCGGCGGGGCGCGCGCGGAGGUGCUGUUCCGCUGCCCGCCCUGCACACCCGAGCGCCUGGCCGCCUGCGGGCCCCCGCCGGUUGCGCCGCCCGCCGCGGUGGCCGCAGUGGCCGGAGGCGCCCGCAUGCCAUGCGCGGAGCUCGUCCGGGAGCCGGGCUGCGGCUGCUGCUCGGUGUGCGCCCGGCUGGAGGGCGAGGCGUGCGGCGUCUACACCCCGCGCUGCGGCCAGGGGCUGCGCUGCUAUCCCCACCCGGGCUCCGAGCUGCCCCUGCAGGCGCUGGUCAUGGGCGAGGGCACUUGUGAGAAGCGCCGGGACGCCGAGUAUGGCGCCAGCCCGGAGCAGGUUGCAGACAAUGGCGAUGACCACUCAGAAGGAGGCCUGGUGGAGAACCACGUGGACAGCACCAUGAACAUGUUGGGCGGGGGAGGCAGUGCUGGCCGGAAGCCCCUCAAGUCGGGUAUGAAGGAGCUGGCCGUGUUCCGGGAGAAGGUCACUGAGCAGCACCGGCAGAUGGGCAAGGGUGGCAAGCAUCACCUUGGCCUGGAGGAGCCCAAGAAGCUGCGACCACCCCCUGCCAGGACUCCCUGCCAACAGGAACUGGACCAGGUCCUGGAGCGGAUCUCCACCAUGCGCCUUCCGGAUGAGCGGGGCCCUCUGGAGCACCUCUACUCCCUGCACAUCCCCAACUGUGACAAGCAUGGCCUGUACAACCUCAAACAGUGCAAGAUGUCUCUGAACGGGCAGCGUGGGGAGUGCUGGUGUGUGAACCCCAACACCGGGAAGCUGAUCCAGGGAGCCCCCACCAUCCGGGGGGACCCCGAGUGUCAUCUCUUCUACAAUGAGCAGCAGGAGGCUCGCGGGGUGCACACCCAGCGGAUGCAGUAGACCGCAGCCAGCCGGUGCCUGGCGCCCCUGCCCCCCGCCCCUCUCCAAACACCGGCAGAAAACGGAGAGUGCUUGGGUGGUGGGUGCUGGAGGAUUUUCCAGUUCUGACACACGUAUUUAUAUUUGGAAAGAGACCAGCACCGAGCUCGGCACCUCCCCGGCCUCUCUCUUCCCAGCUGCAGAUGCCACACCUGCUCCUUCUUGCUUUCCCCGGGGGAGGAAGGGGGUUGUGGUCGGGGAGCUGGGGUACAGGUUUGGGGAGGGGGAAGAGAAAUUUUUAUUUUUGAACCCCUGUGUCCCUUUUGCAUAAGAUUAAAGGAAGGAAAAGUAAA